GCGACGGCGGCGGCGGCGGCGAUCGCCGCGAGGGGUGGUGGGGCCGAAGUCGGUGCCCCCUGGCUCAGUCACGGUGUCCCUCUCUCACUGACUCCCCCUCCUUCCACCACGGCCGCGCAACCCCAGCGCCGGCGGCUUCCUAGGUGGGGCAGGGGACGAGGAGCGUCUCCUCCCGCUGCCGGCGGCCUGAUAAAUGAGGGAUUUCGGGUUUGGGGUGCUGCAGACCGCCCCGCUCCGAAGUAGCAGUCCUGGGCCCCUGUUCUGCGGCGAGGCGUAUGGUCCUUACGCCGUGGGGUCCGUCAACCCGCUGCCCUCCGCCACGCCCUUCGGCCCACUGUCGCCACCACCGUUGCCUGUCACCGGCUUCUUAGAGGCCGCCUCCCCCUUCUCCGUCCCCCUCGGCGGCGGCGCGGGCAGCCCGGCCGCCGCCGCUUCCUCUUCCUCCCCGUUCCUGGCGCAUCAGCAGACCAUGCAGGAUGAGCUGCUUCUGGGGCUGACACAGCAGCCGGCGCGGCCGCUUUCGGGGGCGGCGGCCACGGAGAAACUCCCCGACCACCACCCCGGCGGCGGCACGAUCGCGGGUGUGACCCACCUCCUCCCCUCCCAGGACUUCAAACCGAGUCUGCACCACCCCUCCUCCUCCUCCGCCUCCUCCUGCUGCUGCUGCCGCACCUCCUCCCCGCAGGACUUCAGUAAGCGGCAGCAGCAGCAGCUGAGCAGCCAGAAGAGGAAAGAGUUCAGCCCUCCCCACCUUCCCCACCCUCCGGACUCGAAGCCGCCGCCGCCGCCUCCGCCGCUCCACUGCCCCGGUCGGUUCAGCCCGCCGCCGCCGCCAGCCGGCCCGCUCCUCCAGCCGGCGCAGCUCGCUCAGCGCCAGCAGCAACAGCCGCCGCAGCAGUUCAGCCUCCUGCAUCAGCAGCACCUCUCGCCGCAGGACUUCGCCCCGCGGCAGCGUCCGGCAGACCUGCCCCCGCUCCCGCAGCUCCCUCCCUCGCCGCCUGCAGCCCCGCGGCGCCGCCACGGAGGCGCGGGCAGCCCUCGCAAGACCCCAGCCGCGGGCGAGGGCAGCGCCGCCGAGUCCCCCAAUGCGGGCUUGGCCUCCUCGACGCCGGUGAACCCCGCGCCGGGCUCCAUGGAGUCCCCCAACCACCCUCUGCUCAACAGUCCCAGUAACCUCCUGCCCGGAGGUGCGCUUGGCGCGGGCGCCUUCAGCAGCCUGCAGAGCCCGGACCUUCCACACCCGGGCGGCGGCGGCGGCGGCGGGGGCGGGGGGCCCCCAGGAGGCGGAGGGGGAGGCGGCUCCGCGUCGCCGCCGCCGCUGCCCGGCUUCGGCACCCCCUGGUCGGUGCAGACCGCGUCGCCGCCACCCCAGCCCCAGCAGCCGCCGCCGACCCAGCCGCAGCAGCAGCCGCCGCCACCCCAGCAGCCGCCCCAGCCGCAGCCGCAGCCGCCCGGCUCGUCUGCCACCACCCCGGGCGGCGGCAGCGGCGGCUCGCUCAGCGCCAUGCCGCCGCCCAGCCCCGACUCAGAGAACGGCUUCUACCCCGGGCUGCCGUCGUCCAUGAACCCGGCCUUCUUCCCUAGCUUCUCGCCCGUGUCGCCGCACGGCUGCACUGGGCUCAGCGUUCCGACGAGCGGCGGCGGCGGCGGCGGCUUCGGCGGCCCCUUCUCGGCUACCGCUGUGCCCCCUCCGCCGCCGCCCGCCAUGAAUAUACCUCAACAGCAGCCCCCGCCGCCCGCGGCGCCGCAGCAGCCGCAGAGCCGGAGGUCGCCCGUCAGCCCGCAGCUCCAGCAGCAGCACCAGGCGGCGGCCGCCGCCUUCCUGCAGCAGAGGAACUCCUAUAACCACCACCAGCCUCUUCUGAAACAGUCUCCCUGGAGCAACCAUCAGAGCAGUGGCUGGGGCACUGGAAGUAUGUCCUGGGGAGCAAUGCAUGGCAGAGAUCAUCGUAGAACCGGAAACAUGGGAAUCCCAGGAACUAUGAAUCAGAUAUCUCCAUUGAAGAAACCGUUUUCUGGUAAUGUCAUAGCACCACCGAAAUUUACUCGCUCAACUCCAUCACUGACUCCAAAAUCUUGGAUUGAAGAUAAUGUGUUCAGAACAGACAACAAUAGUAAUACACUCUUACCCUUACAGGUGAGAUCUAGUUUGCAGUUGCCAGCUUGGGGCUCAGAUUCACUCCAAGAUAGUUGGUGCACUGCAGCCGGAACAUCCAGAAUAGACCAGGAUCGAAGUAGAAUGUAUGACAGUUUGAAUAUGCACUCUUUGGAAAAUUCCCUUAUCGAUAUUAUGAGAGCAGAGCAUGAUCCUCUUAAGGGUAG